GCGCAGGCGCUGUGGCGCCCCUAGGCUUGGCCUCCCAGAGACUCGCGGACGCUCACGAUAACCAAGGACGACCGCGAACCAAGGGCAAAAUAACAUGGCAGCCAGACGAAUUACACAGGAGACUUUUGAUGCUGUAUUACAAGAAAAAGCCAAACGAUAUCACAUGGAUGCCAGUGGUGAGGCUGUAAGCGAAACUCUUCAGUUUAAAGCUCAAGAUCUCUUAAGGGCAGUCCCAAGAUCCAGAGCAGAGAUGUAUGAUGACGUCCACAGCGAUGGCAGAUACUCCCUCAGUGGAUCUGUAGCUCACUCUAGAGAUGCCGGAAGAGAAGGCCUGAGAAGUGACGUAUUUCCAGGGCCUUCCUUCAGAUCAAGCAACCCUUCCAUCAGUGAUGACAGCUACUUUCGCAAAGAAUGUGGCCGGGAUCUGGAAUUUUCUCACUCUGAUUCUCGGGACCAGGUCAUUGGCCACCGGAAAUUGGGGCAUUUCCGUUCUCAGGACUGGAAAUUUGCGCUCCGUGGUUCUUGGGAACAAGACUUUGGCCAUCCAGUUUCUCAAGAGUCCUCUUGGUCACAGGAGUAUAGUUUUGGUCCCUCUGCAGUUUUGGGGGACUUUGGAUCUUCCAGGCUGAUUGAGAAAGAGUGUUUGGAGAAGGAGAGUCGGGAUUAUGACGUGGACCAUCCUGGGGAGGCUGACUCUGUGCUUAGGGGCGGCAGUCAAGUCCAGGCCAGAGGUCGAGCUCUAAACAUCGUUGACCAGGAAGGUUCCCUCCUAGGAAAGGGGGAGACUCAGGGCCUGCUCACAGCUAAGGGGGGUGUUGGGAAACUUGUCACAUUGAGAAAUGUGAGCACAAAAAAAAUACCCACCGUGAAUCGUAUUACUCCCAAAACUCAGGGCACUAACCAAAUCCAGAAAAACACUCCAAGUCCUGAUGUGACCCUGGGGACAAACCCAGGGACAGAAGAUAUCCAGUUCCCCAUUCAGAAGAUCCCUCUGGGGCUGGAUCUGAAGAAUCUUCGGCUCCCCAGAAGAAAGAUGAGCUUUGACAUCAUAGAUAAGUCUGAUGUUUUUUCAAGAUUUGGGAUAGAAAUAAUCAAAUGGGCAGGAUUCCACACCAUAAAAGAUGAUAUUAAAUUUUCCCAACUUUUCCAGACUCUCUUUGAACUUGAAACAGAAACCUGUGCUAAAAUGCUUGCCUCAUUCAAAUGUUCCUUAAAACCAGAGCACAGAGAUUUUUGCUUUUUUACUAUCAAAUUUUUAAAGCACUCUGCUUUGAAAACACCCAGAGUUGAUAAUGAGUUUUUAAACAUGCUUUUAGACAAAGGUGCUGUGAAGACCAAAAAUUGCUUUUUUGAAAUCAUAAAGCCUUUUGACAAGUACAUAAUGAGACUUCAAGACCGGCUUCUGAAGAGUGUCACACCUUUGCUUAUGGCCUGCAAUGCCUACGAGCUAAGUGUCAAGAUGAAGACCCUCAGUAACCCCCUGGACUUGGCUCUUGCCCUAGAAACCACCAACUCUCUCUGCCGGAAGUCUUUGGCCCUUUUGGGACAGACAUUUUCCUUGGCCUCUUCUUUCCGGCAGGAGAAAAUCUUAGAAGCUGUCGGCCUGCAAGAUAUAGCUCCCUCACCUGCUGCGUUUCCAAACUUCGAAGACUCCACUUUGUUUGGGCGAGAGUACAUAGACCACCUGAAGGCCUGGCUAGUCAGCAGCGGAUGUCCCCUCCAGGUUAAGAAAGCCGAACCAGAGCCGAUGCGAGAGGAGGAGAAAAUGAUUCCUCCUACGAAACCUGAAAUUCAGGCCAAGGCUCCAAGUAGUCUGAGUGAUGCUGUCCCCCAGCGAGCAGAUCACAGGGUAGUGGGCACCAUCGACCAGCUUGUGAAACGUGUCAUCGAAGGCAGCCUGUCUCCCAAAGAGAGAACUCUUCUCAAAGAGGACCCUGCUUACUGGUUUUUGUCUGAUGAAAAUAGUCUGGAGUAUAAAUAUUACAAGCUGAAGUUGGCAGAAAUGCAGCGGAUGAGCGAGAACUUGCGAGGAGCCGACCAGAAGCCGACCUCAGCAGACUGUGCAGUGAGGGCCAUGCUGUACUCCCGGGCUGUCCGCAACCUCAAGAAGAAACUCCUUCCGUGGCAGCGGCGGGGGCUCCUCCGUGCUCAAGGGCUCCGGGGCUGGAAGGCGAGGAGAGCGACCACCGGGACCCAGACCCUCCUAUCCUCAGGCACCAGGCUGAAACACCACGGCCGGCAGGCUCCAGGCCUCUCACAGGCAAAACCAUCCCUGCCAGACAGAAAUGAUGCUGCCAAGGACUGCCCGCCAGACCCAGUUGGACCUUCUCCUCAGGACCCCAGCUUAGAAGCCUCAGGCCCAUCCCCCAAGCCAGCAGGAGUGGACAUCUCUGAAGCACCUCAGACCUCUUCUCCCUGCCCAUCUGCUGACAUUGACAUGAAGACAAUGGAGACUGCAGAGAAACUGGCUAGAUUUGUUGCUCAGGUGGGACCAGAGAUCGAACAAUUCAGCAUAGAAAACAGCACCGAUAACCCUGACCUGUGGUUUCUACAUGACCAAAAUAGUUCUGCUUUCAAAUUCUAUCGAAAGAAAGUGUUUGAACUAUGUCCAUCAAUUUGUUUCACGUCAUCUCCGCACAACCUUCACACUGGUGGUGGUGACACCACGGGUUCUCAGGAGAGCCCCGUGGACCUCAUGGAAGGGGAAGCAGAGUUUGAAGACGAGCCCCCUCCGCGGGAGGCUGAGCUGGAGAGCCCAGAGGUGAUGCCUGAGGAGGAGGACGAGGACGAUGAGGAUGGGGGAGAGGAGGCCCCCGCUCCUGGAGGGGCGGGCAAGUCUGAGGGCAGCACCCCUGCCGACGGCCUUCCCGGCGAGGCUGCCGAGGACGACCUGGCUGGAGCACCUGCCUUGUCACAGGCCUCCUCAGGUACCUGCUUCCCUCGGAAGAGGAUCAGCAGCAAGUCAUUGAAGGUUGGCAUGAUUCCAGCUCCCAAGAGAGUGUGUCUCAUCCAGGAGCCAAAAGUCCAUGAACCAGUUCGAAUUGCCUAUGACAGGCCUCGGGGUCGUCCCAUGUCCAAAAAGAAGAAACCCAAGGACUUGGACUUCGCCCAGCAGAAGCUGACCGAUAAGAACCUGGGCUUCCAGAUGCUGCAGAAGAUGGGCUGGAAGGAGGGCCAUGGCCUGGGCUCCCUCGGAAAGGGCAUCAGGGAGCCGGUCAGCGUGUACGCAGCAGGCAGCCUGGGGUGGGAGUGGGUGGGGCCUCAGUCCUUCCACCUGCAGCCUGCCGCUUGGCUCCUUCACAGCCAAGAUGGCUUACAGCUGGCAGUUGAUUUUUGUUUUUUAAACAGAAGGCAUCUUCAGAUGAGAAGCUGAUCAUUUACAUGUGCAGGUGUUUACAGGGCUCCUUUCUGUCCUGGUGUAGAUUUUUUAACCAGCUUGUUGGCCCUGGUCAUUUUGGCCACAUUUGUGACCAUCAUAAAAGCUAAGUGGUAUUUCUGUGUAGUUUCCGUCUGGAACUGCUUUCCCAUUCCCGGGAACCCAUAGCCGGGCCAGCCAGGGUCCCGAACACAGGCCCAAAGUUUAUUAAACCCCGAUCAUAACCUCCAGCAGGCAUUUCAUUUAAUACUGAGCUUAGUUCCUGCUGGGUAAGGCAUUCCGAGGUAACCAGGGCCCUCUGGGCACCCCCUCAAAAGCCAGCUCUUCGAGGGUGAGUACUCCUUGUUUCUACUGUGAGUCGCGUCUUGAUUUUCCCUUUCUUUGAUGUCUCAGUGUGUGUCCCAAACACCUGCAUCUCAUGGACUGUUUGUGCCCAUGCCCAGUUCCUGGCAUGCCAGGCCCUGGGCUCAGGUGCACAACUGACUCUCUUUUUCACUCCCUAGGGGAACCCCCUCGGAAGGGGAAGGGUUGGGUGCUGACGGGCAGGAGCACAAAGAAGACACAUUCGAUGUGUUCCGACAGAGGAUGAUGCAGAUGUACAGACACAAGCGGGCCAACAAAUAGGUAUGUUCACAGGCCAGUGUGUAAGGCCGUCUGCCCUCGCUGGCGUGCUGGUAUGCAGAGAAAUUUCCCCCAACAAAGUUGAUGUUCCCUGCUCCCCCAAAAAUGCCACACACAAAAAAAAUCACAAAAUUCUGUGAGGGAAACAAAAGGGUCUAUGGAUGUGGAUAUGCCCCAUUCUUACCUUCCAGGUUUGCUGAAGGAGCAAACCUCACACUGGCCAAGGGCAGAUGCGCAUGGCCUGCCUGGUGCCCCGGCUGUGAGCCCCUCAAGGCCUCCAGGCCAGCCUCCGUGGAUGUGCGUGUGGAAAUAGGCCACGCCUGUCUCUUCUCUUGCUCAAGUUUUCUCUCACAGAUGACAGCCACCUACCACAUAACAUGACCAGCAAACGGACUGUUCCUAGUCCAGAGGGCCUUGCCAUCAUGCAAGUGGAAGGGCGACUGUGACAGCCACUGCCACAGAGGAUGGCAGUUGGCUGUGUCCCUUUGUGAGGGUCUUCAAAUCCUUUUCCUUCUGCAGGGCCUUGGGCCUGUAAAUAUCCUCAUCUUUCUAUUCUUUUUUUUUUUUAGUUGCCCCCUCACCUAAUUUCCACCUCAGUUUUGAACAAAAUCGUUCUCUUCCUGAAUAGAUCAAAACCACUGAUGUGAAAGAUAAGCCUUGAAGCAGCAAUUGCCCUUAAAACAUCAUCCCUGCCCUGGAUCGGCCUGGAGCCAGUGCCCAAGUACGGUUUGGUGUGUACAUGAAAACAAACGUCUCUGCAGUCUCUGGGGCGGAGGUUUCGCUGGCUUUUCUUUCUCUCAAAGAAAAAAACAUGCACCAUUUUCAAUGUGCUUUUGCCUCUCCUCUCUGUUCACAUGCUUUUAGCAGCAAGUCCCCUCCAAAUCUGUCUUGGUUCCCCUUCAGAAGGUGGCGCUGCCCCCGAAAGGCACCUCAGCCUGUGAGUGCUGAGGAACCAGCUCCUCUGGCUGAUUUUCCAGUUGGACUGGCCAUUGCUCUCCAGAAGUGCUCUGUUAGCAAACGUGAUGUGGAAACGAUCACAGAUGGUGUUUUCUCGUUGUUCGCCAGAAUUUAUACGGGGGAGACAAAUUCCCGGUAAUUACCAAGUCUGCACUCGGGUACCAAAGCUCUGAAGCUCUCUGAACAGUUGCCAUACUUGAGUUGAUGAAUGUGUUAUUCAUGGUGUCUCAUCUCAUCAAUGCAUCUUGAGAGACUUAAUGAAAUUUUAGCAACAGUAUAGAAUAGCUCUAUCGGGUGGGGAGUAAUCAUUAAACAGAUGAAAUCGGCCCCAGAUUUACAUGUCUCUUUAGAAUCCACAGUGUAAGCAAACUACAGUUACAAAGGGAUGGGGGUUGUAAACCCUCUGAGACUCUGCACUUUUCGCACGUAUGGCAUCGUCAAGUGCUGUCUUAUUACAGCCUUUGUAAGGAGAGGCAGGCUCCUCCUGGGGUGGGCUCUGCAGCUGCUCUAUUUCCAGGCAUGUGAUCGCCCCCGCUCUCCAGAUUCCCCAGCACUCUGCUGCGUGUAACUCCACUCAAUUCUCCACUCAUCCUUCCUUGUGAAGCAGGAUCGUUGAAGUUUUAAGUAUGGGCAAAAAUCUGGAAAACUUAGGAUCCCUCUGACACCCCAGGAUUAGGGGACACAGCAGUGGCUAGGGCAUCAGCCACAGAACUGAGCGGGAAAUGCCACUUGUAUUGGCUGUAAAGAAAUCCUGGCUUUGGGCCAGGCACAGUGGCUCAAGCCUGUAAUCCCAGCACUUUAGGAGGUUGAGGCGGAUGGAUCACCUGAGGUCAGGAGUUUGAGACCAGCCUGGCCAACAUGGUGUAACCCCGUCUCUACUAAAAAUACAAAAAAAUUAGCCAGGCGUGGUAGCGGGCACCUGUAAUCCCAGCUACUCAGGAGGCUGAGGCAGGAGAAUCACUUGAACCGGGGAGGCAGAGGUUGCAGUGAGCUGAGAUCAUGCCACUCCACUCCAGCCUGGGCGACAGAGCAAGACUCCAUCUCCAAAAAAAAAAAAAAAAAAGGCCGGCACGGUGACUCACGCCUAUAAUUCCAGCACUUUGGGAGGCCGAGGCAGGUGGAUCACGAGGUCAAGAGAUCGAGACCAUCCUGGCCAACAUGGUGAAACCCUGUCUCUACUAAAAAUGCAAAAAAUUAGCUGGGCGUGGUGGCGGGCGCUUGUAGUCCCAGCUACUCAGGAGGCUGAGGCAGGAGAAUCACUUGAACCCGGGAGGCGGAGGUUGCAGUGAGCCGAGAUUGUGCCACCGCACUCCAGCCUGGCAACAGAGCGAGACUCUGUCUCAAAAAAAAAAAAGGAAAUCCUGGCUUUCUUUAAGCCACAGACUUCCUAGGCUGUGGUCCCAGCUCCUUGUCUGCCUGGUCCCUGUCACCUUGCAGUGCCACCACCCCCAGGGGCUCUGCUUGCUUCCAGUGGCUUCUGUAGCUUUGGCAACUGGCAGAUCUUUAUGGCAGUAGAGGUGCCAGCAUGGAGGAUGGAGUUUGGGUUUAUAACCCAACCCUCGAACGAACCAGCCUGUGGGGGCCUGGAGUGGAGCUGGUUUUGGGGAGUCACAGGUGCGGGGGGUUCAUCUUCUCCUUUCUCCUUCUCCUUUCCUGACCCCUCCGACAGCUUCCAUGUUGGCCAUGGGUCAGGUGAAUGGAUGGAGCUCCAAGCGGGGCUCAGCCCAUUGACCCGAGCGAGGCGCACACACCUGCAGCGUGGAUCAAGCGCACUCUCUCCAGCAUCGCCCUGACCAUUCCAUGUGCUUUGUCCUAGCAUGUUCAUUCUUGACUUUCUCCACUUCAUUUUAUUAAAAAGUUAAAUGCUUUAGGAAUCUGUGGCGUGUGGCCACUGACCGCCCCCCACCUCCUGCCGCUCCUCCAAGUUUGAGCUGAGAUGGUUCUGUGAGUCCUUGGCAGGGGUCAAAGGGCACAUCUCCUUGAACCUAGAAAGCCCCCUACACUCUCAGAGGACACCUCUCCUGUGGAUUCAGCGCUGGGGCAGUGAAGGUGUCGGGAGCCAGCAGAGCAUGGUGCGUGCUGCCAGCUGCCGGCCAGCCGGGAUAGAGGAGAUGCCACUGGCCCUCCGUGCCCCCAGCCCCUCCCUCUUAACCGAGGCUGUCCUUGCUCUCUGCAGAGGCCGCUCUGCAGGAUCCUCGUGUCGCGCGUGAUGUGUGGUGGCACAGCCGUGUCAAAGUCACAGUGUCUUUUCUGUCGUUCUAGUUCCAGGGUCACCCCCGAGAGGACAACAGGCAUCUGGAAGUGCUCUCUCGCCACUCUGGGUGCUUUACUGUCUCUGGCUUGUUUCCAUCACUGGAAAUCACUUAGAGAAUUGUAGUGUUUUUGGUCCUUGAUAAAGCCUAGAAGACAUUUGUGAUGUUACAAAAUGGAAGUUUUCUUUUGUUUCUGUUUUUUAAGAUCUAAGAAGUUGUGAAUGUUGUUAAUCAUUUAGCCGUUGCAAUAAAUGUAGAGGAAAUGCA